GAUGGGGAGAGAAGAGGGAUAGGGCCAGCAAGGCAGGGAUCGAACGAGUGUCUGGCAGCCGGGAGCCCAGCGAAGAGAGCGAGCAAGCUUAGGAAAACGAGCGAAGUAAAGGGAGUAGGGGAGACUGAGACUGACCGGUAGCCAGGCAGGCGGACGGACGCACGCCCGGACAGACUGAGCAGGCGCCGGAGAACCACUCACAGGUUCCCCCCGCCUUUCCCUUUGAAAGCUAGGAUUUUGCCUUUCCCGUGGCGCCCGAGAGAGAAUGCUGGACUCUGCCGACUUCAGCGCAAGCUAAGAUUUCUCAGCUAGGGACAAACGAUCAGCCCAAUCCUGAGAAGGGGGGAACCAAGCACCCCGUCCCCAUCCCCCUCCCCUCCCCCGACUAAACUCGGGCGCCAAACCCAGCCCUUCUCUAACCACCCUACUUCCUCCUCUCCUUUCUAGCAUGGUGGCUGUAUGGACAGUCUGACAGAACAGAGACUGACAUCUCCCAAUCUGCCGGCCCCCCACCUGGAACACUACAGUGUUCUGCAUUGCACCAUGACCCUGGAUGUGCAAACUGUAGUCGUUUUUGCCGUGAUUGUAGUCCUCCUGCUUGUCAAUGUCAUACUCAUGUUUUUCCUGGGAACGCGCUGAAUGGAGUCCAGCCACCUGAGCUGUCGCGAACUCUCGCUUUGAUUUCAUCCCGAGAGCCACCGAGAAAAAAAAAAAAUCACAGACAGAGACAGGGAAAGAGAGAGAAAGAACAAGCUUUCUUACUCAGGGGGGAAAACGUUUUGAGCUUCAACAUGGCCUCGCUGUGAUAUGUAUGACCUGAUCACUGGAGAUUCCAUCGUUAGUGCUGAGGCAGUAUGGGAUCACGUCACCAUGGCCAACCGGGAGUUGGCAUUUAAAGCUGGCGACGUCAUCAAAGUCUUGGAUGCUUCCAACAAGGAUUGGUGGUGGGGCCAGAUCGACGAUGAGGAGGGAUGGUUUCCUGCCAGCUUUGUGAGGUCAGAGUCUGCAAAUGCCAUCUGUGUCCCAUCUCAUCUUUGCUGGUUAAAGAAUCAGUCCCAGGGAUAGUCAGAAAAAGCGUAUCAAUAACCACAGACCUUCAGGACUAAUGUGAGGCCCUGUACGCAUACAGCUGCUCUGGGUGAACCAGGAGGAUGAGGUGGAGGAGGGGCCCAGCGAUGUGCAGAACGGACACCUGGACCCCAAUUCAGACUGCCUCUGUCUGGGGCGGCCACUACAGAACCGGGACCAGAUGCGGGCCAAUGUCAUCAAUGAGAUAAUGAGCACUGAGCGUCACUACAUCAAGCACCUCAAGGAUAUUUGUGAGGGCUAUCUGAAGCAGUGCCGGAAGAGAAGGGACAUGUUCAGUGACGAGCAACUGAAGGUAAUCUUUGGGAACAUUGAAGAUAUCUACAGAUUUCAGAUGGGCUUUGUGAGAGACCUGGAGAAACAGUAUAACAAUGAUGACCCCCACCUCAGCGAGAUAGGACCCUGCUUCCUAGAGCACCAAGAUGGAUUCUGGAUAUACUCUGAGUAUUGUAACAACCACCUGGAUGCUUGCAUGGAGCUCUCCAAACUGAUGAAGGACAGCCGCUACCAGCACUUCUUUGAGGCCUGUCGCCUCUUGCAGCAGAUGAUUGACAUUGCUAUCGAUGGUUUCCUUUUGACUCCAGUGCAGAAGAUCUGCAAGUAUCCCUUACAGUUGGCUGAGCUCCUAAAGUAUACUGCCCAAGACCACAGUGACUACAGGUAUGUGGCAGCUGCUUUGGCUGUCAUGAGAAAUGUGACUCAGCAGAUCAACGAACGCAAGCGACGUUUAGAGAAUAUUGACAAGAUUGCUCAGUGGCAGGCUUCUGUCCUAGACUGGGAGGGCGAGGACAUCCUAGACAGGAGCUCGGAGCUGAUCUACACUGGGGAGAUGGCCUGGAUCUACCAGCCCUACGGCCGCAACCAGCAGCGGGUCUUCUUCCUGUUUGACCACCAGAUGGUCCUCUGCAAGAAGGACCUAAUCCGGAGAGACAUCCUGUACUACAAAGGCCGCAUUGACAUGGAUAAAUAUGAGGUAGUUGACAUUGAGGAUGGCAGAGAUGAUGACUUCAAUGUCAGCAUGAAGAAUGCCUUUAAGCUUCACAACAAGGAGACUGAGGAGAUACAUCUGUUCUUUGCCAAGAAGCUGGAGGAAAAAAUACGCUGGCUCAGGGCUUUCAGAGAAGAGAGGAAAAUGGUACAGGAAGAUGAAAAAAUUGGCUUUGAAAUUUCUGAAAACCAGAAGAGGCAGGCUGCAAUGACUGUGAGAAAAGUCCCUAAGCAAAAAGGUGUCAACUCUGCCCGCUCAGUUCCUCCUUCCUACCCACCACCGCAGGACCCGUUAAACCACGGCCAGUACCUGGUCCCCGACGGCAUCGCUCAGUCGCAGGUCUUUGAGUUCACCGAACCCAAGCGCAGCCAGUCACCAUUCUGGCAAAACUUCAGCAGGUUAACCCCCUUCAAAAAAUGAUACCUACAGGGAGGCAGAUAAUUUUAAAAUAAAGUAAAUAAAAUUAUAUUUAUAGAUGGACCUUUUUUCGGAGAAGCACUGUUGAAAUUUAUACACACACACACACACAGAGACCCUUGAGUACACAUACACACACACACACACAGACACACACACACACACACACACACACACACACACAGAGAGAUAAGGAACAAAAGUGUUUUCUGUUGUUUUGGGGAAGUGAAAUAUGUGGUUGGUAGGAAGAGGUACCAAUGACUUCCAAACAUGUGAUUCCGUCUUAAAAGUUUUCCAUUUUUACCCUGUCCCCCUUCCCUUUGCUUUCAGAAGUUGACAUUUCUAUUCAUUGCUUUUCUUGUUAAGAUAAUCUCUUUACUCCCCUGUGAGUGAUUCACUGCCUUGUCAUUAUUACGAUAGAUGUGUUUGUAUUGUUUUUUUUCUGAUGAUACUGAUGUUGAUGAAUUUUUAAUUUUAUUUGAUGUGGUAGAGUUGGGAGGUUUCAGGGUUUUUUCCCCUCUUUUACUUUCCAUUGAGGAAGGGAAUGAGCUCCUUUCUCCUCUCCUUCAGCCAAUCAUUAUCAAAUGUUCCUUCAGCCCUGCAGUUGCCCCAAAUAACCUUUUUUCAGCAUCCUCUGUCCUCAGUCAUGCCAGUCUGGACAUGCUCUGUUGUGCCCUGUGACAAAACUGCUCAGUAUUCCUAUUGCUUUUACUGUGUUUUAGGUACUGUGAAGGGAUCAAAAAACCAAACAGAAGCAAGGGAGUAUCAGACUAUGAUGAUGCUGGAGUGGACUUCUGUUCAGGGAACAUUUUGCAUUCAGGCUGUUUCUUCUAUCACUGGGGUUUCCCAUGUUGCAGCACUUCUGGGUCGUUGCAAUUUUGCAUCUAGGAGUUAGUUUGAUCGAGUUAUUCUCUUUUUUCAAGUCACUUUUGUUAUAGGUCUCCCCCUAGGCCUGUCUCUCCCUUAGCCCAAAAGAUCUGAACUGGAAGCAGAGGUUGAGAUUCUGCCUCCCAGGAGAGGGAUUUACCUGCCCCCUAGUACCAGAUAGGUUUAGGGCAGUGAUCUCUACAGCAAUCAGUUCAGUGUCCUGGUUGUCCCUGCUCCCAUUUACAGAUGUUUGGGCAGCAUUGAUAGAAGUAUGGAGGGGUUCAAGACAGAGCCCACCUGAUCAAGAUCAUCAGCUACCUUCAAAUUAUUGACCUGGACAGGGUCCAAGUCUGAUAGUAACCUUUUACAAGAAAGAACAGGGAUGGGAAUGGAAAGAGAUAGCCUUGAUCCACAGUAUUGUACCUGCAUUUUCUACCACCCUAAAAUUGUGUGAGACUUCUCCCAUUGUUAACAGAUUGCAUGGACAAUCUUCCCUGGCUUCUUUCUUUCCCUCUCUCUUUCUUCUUUCUCCUGCCAUCCUAGCACAGGAGGAUUUUUGGUAUUGAUAUAGUUAAAGCUGUUCUGGCACUCAAAGAAGGCCGUGUUUCCAACAUCCUCUCAUCCCAGGACAUUUGGGGCAAGUGAGUUAGGGGCCCAGGGGCAAUUUUCCCUCUGAAUAACGUGUCUGAGGCAGGGAUGCUACCCUCAGGCUCGCUUUUGGCCAGCUUUUUGCUUGGGAAAAUCUAACUUCUUUCACAAGGAGGCAGGCUUCCUAUGGAUGUUGGAGUACCUGUUUUUCCUCCACACAUAGCCCUUUUCAUGGAUAGACCUUGAACAACAAAAAGGGUAUAAGGGAAUAAGGAUGAACUCUGCUGUGAAGAGCAAGCCACUGUAGUGAGGAAUGUGGAGACUGGGAGUCUGUCCUAAACCCCAUGGGAGAAGACUUCAUCAUGACAGGACUUCAGCUUACCAAGCAGCAGCCAUAGCUGUGUGGAGGCUUCAGCAUAGCUAGCAUGUUUACUGCUCUAUGCCUCCUGAUCCAGACCAGGCAUUGCCCAGCCUGGGAAUCUUUUCUUUGUGGGAAUCAAAUUACAAGCUAUUUAAGUUUAUAUUCCAUCACAACCAAGUCAGACUUGUAUUAUAAGUCAAGGAUGAGCCUGAUCUGGGGAGAGGGCCGGGGCUCGGGACUGGCCACCACUGUUCAGCACAUGACCUAACUACGUAAGCCUCUUUGGCAAGGGUCCUGGUGCCCAGCACCCAGGCUAAAAUAUCCUGUCUGGCAGAGUGUUUUGGUAGCUAUGCAGGCCUCCCUUCAGUGUACCUCUUUUUCCAACUUCUCACUCCUCCUUACUAGGCUUGGCCUUGACAUGCUUCUUCGAGGGUUGGCAGCACACCGGGAGGGGAUGCUUGGACAAGUUUCUGGGCCUACAUUUCUUGACUAGGCCCUCUCAUUUCCUCCCUCCUUGGGGCUUCUGCCCAGGGCUCCAGGAUCAGGGAUAUUACUUCUCAACCCGCACUUCUCCUCUACUGAACCCACUGGCAUCACCUGAUGCCACUAAUUUGUGAACAACAAGAAAUCAUUUCCCCAUUGGUUGGAGUAUUCCCUCAGCCUAUAGCAUCAAAGCAGACCAGUGGCCAACAGCCCCAAGGGGAGCCCAAUUAAAUACCUGGGUUCAGUAUCCUAACCUGUUAUGUCCUGACAGCAAUGGUAACCCCAGUAAUUCUGUAAUGUUGUAAUUUCCGCAUGGCCCUGAGCUCCCUUUUCCUCAACUCAGUGAGGCCAGGAUUUGCUCUCCAAAAGGCUUUGCUAGUGUGUUCAAUGGGACCUGCUGUGGGGAGUCCUAAGACAGACAUCUAAUUAUUCUCUCUUUUUCCCCCCCUCUCUAUGUGUAUAUUUCUAAUGGAUCUAUAAGAACAGCAACAAGAGAGUUCUAACAAUUCUAGUGUGAAGCCAAAUAGUGAUCUUUUAGUGCUUUGGGGAUGGGGUGGGCUGGGGUGGAUGGAUGGGCAACAGUGACUUUGAUUACCCUUGCUGCUCUGCAUUUGCCAGUUUAUUCUUUUGUUUCUUUUAUCUGACUGACUCUGUCAAACAAGUGUCAAAGUUGUGUGUUAAAAAAUGUUUAACAAAAAAAAUGUUGUAAUGACACAAAGCCUUAUGAAAAUAUUUAUGGAGUUCAAUAAAAGAAGUAAAAAGACA